GACCCGGUCGCUGUGGCAACGCGGCGGGACCUGGCCAGCGCUGCUGGCGGGCGUUAGGGUAUUUCUGGAAAACUCAAACUGUUUUUCCUCUACUCUGAUACCACAAGAAUCAUCAGCACAGAGGAAGACUUCUGUGAUCAAAUGUGGUGGGAGAGGGAGGUUUUCACCAGCACAUGAGCAGUCAGUUCUGCCGCAGACUCGGCGGGUGUCCUUCGGUUCAGUUCCAACACCGCCUGCCUGGAGAGAGGUCAGACCACAGGGUGAGGGCUCAGUCCCCAAGACAUAAACACCCAAGACAUAAACACCCAACAGGUCCACCCCGCCUGCUGCCCAGGCAGAGCCGAUUCACCAAGACGGGAAUUAGGAUAGAGAAAGACGGCCACCAUGCUGCCACUGGGCUCAGAGCCCGCCCUGAAUGAGCUGCUGCUUCGCAAGGAGGAGGAGUGGAGGGCGCUGCAGGCACACCGCACCCAGCUGCAGGAGGCGGCUCUGCAGGACACACGGAGCCAGCUGGAGGAGGCGCAGGGGAAACUGCGGUGCCUGCAGGAGGACUUUGUCUACAACCUUCAGGUGCUGGAGGAGCGGGACCUCGAGCUGGAGCGCUAUGACGCCGCCUUCGCCCAGGCCAGGGAGUGGGAAGAGGCCAGGCGGGCAGAGGUGAGCGAGCUCAAGAUAGAGGCAGCUAAGCUGAGGCAGGCGCUAGCCAGAGAGGCCAGGAAGGUGGAGGAGCUGCAGCAGCAGCAGCAGCUGGCAUUCCAGGAGCAUCGCCUGGAGCUGGAGCGCGUCCACAGUGACAAGAAUGGUGAGAUUGACCACCACCGGGAACAGUAUGAAAAUCUAAAAUGGACACUGGAGAGAAAACUUGAGGAGCUCGACGGUGAGCUUGCUCUGCAGAGACAGGAACUGCUGCUGGAGUUUGAAUCGAAAAUGCGGAAGAGGGAGCACGAAUUCCGUCUGCAGGCUGACAACAUGAGCAACACAGCCUUGUCCCGGGAGCUUAAGGUUAAACUACUGCACAAAGAGCUGGAGGCUCUGAAGGAAGCCGGGGCAAAGGCUGCAGAGAGUCUGCAGAGGGCAGAGGCCACCAACGCCGAGCUGGAGAGGAAGCUCCAGAGCCGAGCCGGGGAGCUCCAGGACCUGGAGGCCAUGAGCCGCGCCCGGGUAAAGGAUUUAGAGGAUAAACUUCACUCUGUGCAGCUAACCAGGAAGAAGGAAGAGGAAACAUUUAAGAGGAAGCAUGAGGAGCUCGACCGUCUGGCCAGGGAGAAGGAUGCAGUGCUGGUGGCGGUGAAGGGAGCCCACGUGGAGCAGCUGCAGGAGCUGCAGACCAGGGUUCUGGAGCUGCAGGCCCACUGCGAGACCCUCGAGGCGCAGCUCCGCAGGGCAGAGUGGAGACAGGCUGACACCGCCAAGGAGAAGGACGCUGCCAUUGACCAACUUCGUGAAGAUGCAUCAACUGUAAAAUCUGCCUGGGAUGCUCAAAUUGCUCAACUAUCUAAGGAGAUGGUCUCCAGAGACCUUCAGAUUCAGACGCUGCAGGAAGAAGAGGUGAAGCUCAAGGCACAGGUGGCCCGAUCCCAGCAGGACAUUGAAAGGUACAAGCAACAGCUGUCCCUGGCAGUGGAAAGGGAGCGGAGCCUGGAGCGUGAUCAGGUGCAGCUGGGCCUGGACUGGCAGCGCCGCUGUGAUGACAUUGAAAGGGACCAGAUCCAAAAGUCAGAGGCCCUGAUUCAGGGUCUGAGCAUGGCAAAAAGUCAGGUUGCUGCCAAGCUGCAGGAGACAGAGCAGGCGCUACAGGAGCAGGAGGUGGUGCUGAAGGCCGUGACCCUGGAACGAGACCAGGCCGUGCAGGCCCUGAGGAUGCAUGGGCUCCCCAGACCAGGGGCACAGAUGCUUCUCAGGCAGCAUGAAGAAGAAAUAAGUAAAGACUUUCCAUCCAGUGAGAUCCAGCGGCUCCGAGAGCAGAACACGAGCUUGCGAAACGCGAUUGCCCAGAUGAGGAAAGAAAUGGAGGCUCUAAGCCAUCAGAUUCCUCCUCCCAUCCAGACAGCGGCAGAGAGCACAGAUGCAAACCAGCCUGACCCAGAGGCUGGGGGAGAUGCCGCCACUCCUGAUUAUGUUCUGGCCCUUGAAGCAGAAAUACGAACUCUAAAGCAUAAGUUUAAAACUCUGGAAAAGCAUCUAGAAGAUGUGUUGGAUCCUUUAAAGAUGUCCUCACCUCAUGCUGAGUCUCAGCCCAGCGUCCGCACCUCGACAGAGACGACUGGAGGGUCUGCCCAAGCUGGUCAAGCCGGAGGGUCUGUCCAAGCUGGUCAAGCAGGAGGAUCUGUCCAAGCUGGCCCAGUAUCCUCUGGACUGGCACUCAGGAAGCUCGGGGACAGAGUGCAGCUCCUAAACCUGCUGGUGACACGACUCAGACAGAAGGUGCUGCGGGAACCCCUGGAGCCGGCCGCUCUCCAGCGUGAGCUUCCCCGUGAGGUGGACCAGGUACACCUGGAGGUUUUGGAGCUGCGGAAGCAGGUGGCUGAGCUGGGGAAGCAUCUCAGGAUAGCCCAGCACGGGGGAGCGGAGCCUUCAGGCAGGAAGCAGCCCCCAGCCUCGGACGCCGUGGCCCUUGGGAGAGAGGUGGGUGCCCGCUAGCUCCUCCUGCCACCCGCCGAGGUUCCUGCCACAGAAACCGUCCUUGCCUGUGCUCUGCCAGCGUUGCUGUCUGUAUGCCCUGGGAGCUCAGGUGGGACGAGGGCUGCAGUGAAGGCCGUGCCUGGAAGUGGGCCCUGCUCCACCCCCUCUCCCCAUUCCUCCGCCUUCUUCCUCCACACGCCUCCUCUUCUCCUGGUCCUUCACCUUGAUGCCCCGUUGGUGGGGGGCGGGACGGGCCCAUCCCAGUCCUCCCUUCAGCUAACAGCAUCUUGUGUUGGAAACGCACACACUGAAGGUGGCUCAUGUUUGCUUUAAUGCAGGGCCUUGACGGCCUGCUGAGGGGGCGUCUGCGUGCACAGCCAUGCCUGCCCCAUGCCUAGCGUUGGGCCCUCCCUGCGUGGGGAGGGGCCCACAUGGCCCUCACUGCUGCGUUCAGAGCCACACAGCUGCUCCAGGCCAUGGCACUCCUAUCCUGGUUUUGGUCAGGCCCUUGGCCCCGAGGGAGUGACCCCCAACUCCAUGGCUGGGUUUGAGCCACAGCUCUGAGCUGUGGAGACGACCCCAGGUCCUGAUUCUGCAGCUUGGCAGAGCCGACCAGCAGGGCCCCCUUCUUCCUACCUAAGGCCAGAGGGAAAGGCUGUGAAGGACAGGCUGCCCGGCCUCCCUGACUUCGUACCCUAGACUGUUGGUAACUGGGAUAACUGUAGUGACCUAUGACCUGUGGUAACCUAUAGUUACCAAUAGUGACCUAUGAAUCCACAGAAGGUUUUGGGGACAGUAGAUGAUGUCUGGAAAGCACAAAGUGGAAGACAGCGUGGAUCCCCAGGGCACCGUGCUUGGGGAGCAGAUCCCCAGGGACUCAGGCUGGAAUAGAGUGGACUGAGGAAGAUGCGGCCGUGGCUGUCUCAGGCUCCAGGACAGUGAGGAGCAGGCCAGAGCUGCCUUGGCAUGGGAUGGGCAAGACCAUAAGGAUGCCUCAGGGGUACAACAGGGCAGGUAUGGGAAGGCCGAGGGAGCCUGAGGCCCUAGCAGGUGCUCAGCCAGUGCGCACAGGAAGGGCUGAGCUGGUCGGUAAGAUAUUGAGCUGCACCUGCCCCUGUACCUGUUGGUAAGGAGGUCUUGUCCUCAGGGGUCUCCAGCACCCUAGCCCUCCUGGGCUCCCAGUCCAGCCACUCCAGGGUGGCUCCUGCCCGGUGGGGGCUGUGGCCCUUGGGCCAGCUGGCAGCACAGCCAGGGGUAAGCAUGUCUGUACCCCCACACAUCUCCCACCCACCUGAGCGCCAUGUGUUCCCGGACACGGGCGGGCGCCUCCUUGGGCAGCAAGGGGCCCCAGGAGCUCUCACUGUUGGCCCUUGCGUAGUUCACUGUCUUCCCACUUGUUUAGAAUGAAGGGGCAAGAAUUUAUACAAAUAAGCAGAAUUUUUUCUUUCUUUUUUUUUUUUGAGACAGAGUCUCACACUGUCGCCCAAUCUGGAGUGCACUGGCGCUAUCUUGGCUCACUGCAACCUCCUCCUCCCGGGUUCAAGCAAUUCUCCCGCCUCAGCCCCCUGAGUAGCUGGGAUUACAGGUGCACCACGCCCGGCCAAUUUUUGUGUUUUCAGUAGAGACAGGGUUUCACCAUGUUGGCCAGGCUGGUCUCAAACUCCUGGUUUCAAGUGAUCUGCCUGCCUCAGUCCCCCAAAGUGGUGGGAUUACAGGUGGGAUUAUAGGCACAGUGGCCCACUGUGCCUGGCCCAAAUAAGCAGAAUUUUAAAUUGAGAGAUGAAGCCACCUGCAGCCCAAUCCCAGUUAUUGGAGCUAAGGCACAGGCGGGGCAUACACUCCAGGCUCUGUGUCUACAUGCAUGGAGGCGACAGUCGGGCUCCAGGCUCCUCCUGGGUCUGAGCAUCCUGUGGCCGGGCUCUCCACCCAGGCGAGGCCCACCUGGGCUCUGUCCUCUGCCAAGCAGCAUGGCUGAGCUCCUGGAGACGAGGGCGGGCCCAGGUCCUUGCUGCUUGCUGCUGGGAAAGGAGCCCAGACGGAGAAGGGGCCAUGUUGGGGCUGGACCCUCAGGUAGAGGAUCAAUGUGUCCGUUAUGUUGGGUAUAGAGAGAAGUGGGUAGAGCUGCAUGUGCAUCUGAUCCCAGCUCUGUCCUGAGAGGGCCCACAGCCCGGACUCAGCCACAGCAGAUGCCAGUUCCACAGUUCCAGGCGCUAGUUCCAUGGUUCCUGCCCUGCUCACAGGAGCCCGGGCUCUAGCAUGGAGGCAGGUUCGGAAGGCACAGGAAGCAGCUGAAAGGGGUCCCCAAGGACCAGAACUAGGCCAAUAGGCAGUGACGUUGAAGACCACAAUCCACUGACUCAACCAGGAAAUCAUGGGUCCAGGCUGAUAGCAAUGGACAGAUCGGUCAGGGGAACGGGGCACUCUUCCACGCGAGAGUGCCAGCCAAGGAACGCGACAGGAACGGCGCGCCGGGCGACCACGGAUGGGUGCUGAACCAGAGGGAUUCCCAUCAGACGGAUGCGAAGCAGCAUCUCCCCACACGUGACUUCUUAUUUCCAAGGGAAAUGCUGGCUUUCCAGUGGAGCAGCCUGUUUGACCCCAGCUGACCCGAGUGAUCAGAGCUCCCAUCGCCAGUGCUGGGAUGCGCCCGUGUCACGCGCCUCUGGGCGGGUCGCACUGAGACGGCACAGACUCGCGCUCGGGGUCCCUGCCAAAAAUGCAGAACCUGAGCUUAUGCAUGAGGAGACCUCAGGCAAGCCCAAACAGAGGGACAUCUGCAGAUGAGCGGGUCUAGAUGCUUGGCGAGUGCCCAAACAUGGAAGCUGGGGAGCCACUCCAGUUAGGAGACCUGGGAGACCCCAUGUAGAAAUGCCAGGUGGGACCCUGGACCCUGCACAGGAGAGACAGCGUCAGGGCAUCAUCUGUAGAAACGCCACGUGGGACCCUGGGCUCUGUACAGGAGAGACGGGCAUCAAGUCAUCAUCCGUAGAAACGCCACGUGGGACCCUGGACCCUGCACAGGAGAGACGGCGUCAGGGCAUCAUCCGUAGAAACACCACGUGGGACCCUGGACCCUGCACAGGAGAGACGGUGUCAGGGCAUCAUCUGUAGAAACACCAUGUGGGACCAUGGACCCUGCACAGGAGAGACAGUGUAGAAAUGCCACGUGGGACCCUGGACCCUGCACAGGAGAGAUGGCGUCAGGGCGUUAUCUGGACGGUUGGUGACAUUUGCACACGGGCCACGGACCAGGUCACGUAUUGUGUACACCCACCCAAGUACUGAGGUGUGACGCGGCACUGCGUCUCCAGCCUACCUCCUGUAGUGCAGGAAGCCAGUGCAGGGUGGGUGAGGAAGUGCACAGGGGUCCAGGGACUGUCCCACAGCACUCCUGACGAAAGCUGGUCCCCUUCCACGGCCCUAGCCAAGGAGCCAGGUCUGCAAAGCUGGGACCAGGUGUGUGCGGAGGCACGUGUUCCCACUUCUCCCAUGGCAGAGGGAGAGCCUGUGGACAACAGUGGGGCACUCUGCUCCCAGGCAGGUCCCACUGGGCUGAGCCGCACAGCCUGGCUUUGGGCUUCCCUGACUGCACCACCCACAUCAGCUGCCUCUAGCCCUUAAAAUACAAAACUUCCCCCAGUCACUGGCCGCCAGGGCUGAGUUGGGGGAUGUGUUACAUCCCUGGGUCCACUGGGGGGCAGUGUUGGCCAUGGUGUUGGUGCUGGCUCUGCCGAGAGGCGUUGGAGUGGCUGUGUGGGGCGGUGAGCGCCGGCCCAGCCUGAUGGAACCCACUGUACCAGGCCCAGGCCUCAGCCUCUGAGAAGGACUUCCCUGUGUCACUCACUCAUACAUGUCCUCAGGACGUGAAGACAUUUCAGCAGACCAAAGUUUCCUUCGAAUUUUCUUCGAAUCGUCCAGAUACUUGGAGACAUCUCCUCCUCACCUGUGGGGUGCUGGGGCAGUCCUAGGCGUGGGGGCAGAUGGGUGGACAGCUGCUGCUGCCCUGCUGGGGGUGGGCAGCCCUUGGAGCACACAGUGGUGAAGACAUUCCUGAAUAUGUCUCAGGCUGUAGAAAUCUUAUUUUGUGGAAAGAUUUUAGAGAAUCAUCAAAAUAAACUUUUACCAAAUAACAUUUUACCAGAAACUGAA